AGCUGAGGUGUGGGUGUUCGUUUCUCAGGUGAAACAUGGCUAAAAGCUUACGGAGUAAGUGGAAAAGAAAGAUGCGUGCUGAAAAGAGAAAAAAGAAUGCCCCAAAGGAGGCCAGCAGGCUUAAAAGUAUUCUCAAACUAGACGGUGAUGUUUUAAUGAAAGAUGUUCAAGAGAUAGCAACUGUGGUGGUACCCAAACAUUGCCAAGAGAAAAUGCAAUGUGAGGUAAAAGAUGAAAAAGAUGACAUGAAAAGGGAGACUGAUACUAAGAGAAACAAAAAGACUCUUCUAGACCAGCAUGGACAGUACCCAAUAUGGAUGAACCAAAGGCAAAGAAAAAGGCUGACGGCAAAGCGAGAGAAAAGAAAGGGGAAAAGCAAAGCAAAAGCAGUGAAAGUGGCAAAGGGUUUGGCGUGGUAGACUCUUAAAACCUUGGAAAAUGCCACAUGGGAUAGAUGAUGGAUUAGAAUGUAUAUACAUGUAUACUUUGAUUUCAGCUGCCACCAAAUGAAAACCAUUUGUUUUCCUAUUUUAACUUGGCCUUUUUUCUUCAAUUCAAACCCAGCAUAACUCCUGAAGUUUGUUUUGGGAACUUGAAUAAAAUAUUUUCUUUGAUACAAAAAAAAAAAAGAAUUAGGUUAAAAAGAAUUAGGUAAUUCUUUUUUUAUUAGGUAGAAUCCUGUUAGGUAGAAUUAUUUUAUAGAUGAUAAAAGUAAGGGAAGUUAAACACCUUGCUCAAGGUCAUUUGUGUAACAAGAAUGAGUGCCAGCAUUUGCACUCAGACAGUGUAGCUCUAGAGUGUGUGCCCUUCUCAAGUACUCCAGCAUGAAUGCAGAGUAUUCGCACUGAGCCACAGAGGCAAGCAGUCAGGAGAGUACGCAUCUGAAACGGUGCUGUGGGGUGUUGAACUUGCAUGGUGAGUCGCAUGUGGGAUCAGCUUUCUAGAAGUAUUGAUUAUGGCAGAUUGAGAUGGUAAAACUCUGACUCUCAGUCACAGAUACCUUGAGAAAUACUAUAUUAUUAAUAUACUACUACUUGCUGGUGGGGGUUUGUGGAAGCUGUUGCAGUUGACAAGGUAAGAGAUGAUGGUGACUUGGACGAGUAUAGCAGAGGAGUAGAAAGAAGUGGUCAGGGCCAGGCGUGGUGGCUCAUGCCUGUAAUCACAGCACUUUGGGAGGCCAAGGUGGGUGGAUCACAAGGUUAGGAGUUUGAGACCAGCCUGGCCAACAUAGUGAAACAAAAAAUUAGCUGGGCAUGGUGGCAGGCACCUGUAAUCCCAGCUACUUGGGAGGCUGAGGCAGGAGAAUCACUUGAACCUGGGAGGCAGAGGUUGCAAUGAGCCAAGAUUGCGCCAUUGCACUCCAGCCCGGGCGACAGUGUGAGACUCCAUCUCAAAAAAAGAAAAAAAAAAAAAAAAGAAAGAAAAAAGUUGUCAGAUUAGGACAGGCACAGUGGCUCAUACCUGUAAUUUCAGCACUUUGGGAGGCCGAGGUGGGUGGAUCACUUGAGGUCAGGAGUUUGAGACCAGCCUGGACAACAUGGUGAAGCCCUCUCUCUACUAAAAAUACAAAAAUUAGCUAAACACAGUGGCACGUGCCUGUAAUCCCAGCUGCUUGGGAGACUGAGGCAGGAGAAUCACUUAAACCCGGGAAGCGGAGGUUGAAGUGAGCCAAGAUCGCACCACUGCACUCCAGCUGUGUGACAGAGCAAGACUCCAUCUCAAAAAAAAAAAAGAAGAAGAAGAAGUGGUCAGAUUCAGGACGUGUUUUGAGGAUAAGUGGUGGAUUUAAUGUAGGGCUUGAGAAAAUGCCAUUGUGUAUGACUGACUGGUGUUUGAAUCCUUUAUCAUAUCCCAGGGCCGGUCUAGGACACAUAAUUGUGUGUGCCUAGGCAUUCUUCCCAGUUUGUUGUGGCUGCCCUGCCCAAGCCCACAUCACCUAUUAGCUUCACGUCCUUCUCU